AGCACCCAAUUAGGAGAGGCCGGGAUAAGACUUGAGUUUUGCGGCUGCUGCUUUUGGGUUGGGAGUCCGGGGGCCUUUCUCCGGGGAUGAAGGCGAUACCCUCAUCCCUUUCCAGGGCAGAGGAACCCCGUGCCCCGCCCCUUUCCUGUCAUCUCAGACGAACGCAGCGACAUCCUGAGGAAGGCGCAUCACAAUAGGGGAUAAGGUGGUGGGCAGCCUCCCUCUGGGUGAAGAGGAGUGAGACCCCACUAACGUGCUGCGUGGUUUUAUGUUGUAACCAUUUUACGUGUGGUUAUGGGUGCUACAUGUGUGCUUUCAGAGCAGUAGUGUGAGGAAGCUUGGAGUGGGAUGGCAGGACGGCCUCAUCCCUAUGAUGGUAACUCCAGUGAUCCAGAGAAUUGGGAUCGGAAAUUGCAUAGUAGACCUCGUAAACUUUAUAAACAUUCAAGUACUUCCUCGCGUAUUGCUAAAGGAGGAGUUGACCACACCAAAAUGAGUCUACAUGGUGCUAGUGGGGGACAUGAGAGAUCAAGAGAUAGACGAAGGUCAAGUGACAGAUCACGAGAUUCAUCUCAUGAAAGAACGGAGUCUCAGCUCACUCCUUGUAUUAGAAAUGUGACUUCUCCAACACGACAGCACCAUGUUGAACGAGAAAAAGAUCACAGUUCCUCUCGUCCAAGCAGUCCGCGUCCUCAAAAAGCAUCCCCAAAUGGUUCCAUUAGCAGUGCUGGGAACAGCAGCAGAAACAGUAGUCAGUCAAGUUCAGAUGGUAGCUGUAAGACAGCUGGGGAGAUGGUGUUUGUAUAUGAAAAUGCAAAAGAAGGAGCUCGGAAUAUAAGAACGUCAGAACGAGUGACACUAAUAGUGGAUAACACUAGAUUUGUUGUAGACCCAUCCAUUUUUACUGCACAGCCAAAUACAAUGUUGGGCAGGAUGUUUGGAUCUGGCCGAGAACAUAACUUUACACGACCCAAUGAGAAAGGAGAGUAUGAGGUGGCAGAGGGAAUUGGUUCCACUGUGUUUCGAGCGAUUCUGGAUUACUAUAAAACAGGAAUAAUCCGUUGUCCUGAUGGCAUAUCUAUUCCUGAACUGAGAGAAGCAUGUGACUAUCUUUGUAUCUCUUUUGAAUAUAGCACUAUUAAAUGUAGAGAUCUCAGUGCCCUAAUGCAUGAGUUAUCAAAUGAUGGUGCUCGUAGACAAUUUGAAUUUUAUCUGGAAGAAAUGAUCCUCCCUCUCAUGGUAGCUAGUGCCCAGAGUGGGGAACGGGAAUGUCAUAUAGUGGUGCUUACAGAUGAUGAUGUGGUUGAUUGGGAUGAAGAAUAUCCACCACAGAUGGGAGAAGAAUAUUCACAAAUUCACCUUUUAAGGGAGAUAACUCAACCCGAAAGAGAGAAGGCGAGGAAUGUCCAUCAGUCUAACUCCCUGAAGUUCUCAGCACAUUUGGAAGACUCAACAUGUUUUAUUUAUAGCACAAAAUUAUAUAGAUUUUUCAAGUAUAUUGAAAACAGAGAUGUGGCCAAGUCAGUUUUGAAGGAGAGGGGUCUUAAGAAGAUUAGAUUGGGAAUAGAAGGUUAUCCUACCUACAAAGAAAAAGUAAAGAAAAGGCCUGGAGGCCGCCCAGAAGUGAUCUACAACUAUGUCCAAAGACCCUUUAUUCGAAUGUCCUGGGAGAAGGAAGAAGGAAAGAGUCGGCAUGUAGACUUUCAGUGUGUAAAGAGUAAAUCUAUCACCAAUCUUGCAGCAGCUGCAGCAGACAUUCCCCAGGACCAGCUGGUAGUCAUGCAUCCAACUCCACAAGUGGAUGAGCUGGAUAUUCUCCCUAUCCAUCCCCCUUCUGGCAACAGUGACCUCGAUCCUGAUGCACAGAAUCCAAUGCUGUGAUGCUGAUCUUCCUUGAAACCAUAGCAUGCUACUCUUCACAGUGACGUUGUACUCUCCUCAUUCUGCACUGCAAGGCCACUCUUCUUCAUUGUGAGAUGCACAUAACAAUGUUUAGGAUAUUGCAGUGUAGGCUUUUUUAAAGACCAAAGGUAGCUGAAUGGUUUUUUUUUAAAUGAGUACAACUCUAGCAUUUUGAAGUUCCAGUUGUAAAUGUAUUUGUUUACCAGUAGGUUUGUGAAAUUGGUUCUUUGUAUGGGGGAUGGUCCUUUUUCACACAGCUAGGUCUUUUCAGAAGUGGUGGAAAUUGGCAGCUGGGGUACUUUCAGUUUGGACUGAUAUUCAUCACACCUCAGAUAAAAUGCAGAGUAAUAUAUAGUUGCACUUUAUAAAUGGUGGUUAAAUGGAAAUGUUCAAGCCAUUUUAUAGUUGUGAUGCACAAUAUAAUUUAAGUGCUUCUGUCAAAGUAUUCCUCCAGUACAAUUUGUAUAGUUUGCUGCCCUUGAUGAGCAAAAAGUAUUUAUCUUGGGCUUAUCUGAAUGAUCAGGAUGAGAUUUAAUGCCCAUAUCUUACCAGUUCAGUUAUCUCCAGAGCCAUUUCACCCUUUAGAGUGAGUCACAUGCAGGGAGUGUGAAUGUCAGAGGUGGUUUAUUAUCCAGUCUGCCUUACCCUUAAUCUGUUCACAGAUAUUUAUUUACUAAUGCUUUUUUUUUCUUAAGAGUUAUGGGAUAGGAAAAUGAAGUGUUUGCUCUUCAUUUACUAAAUGAUUGUAAACUUGAGUUUUUCAUCAAAAUAAAAUUCCAUUGUUUUAAUGUUUCUGACCAAA